ACCAGAUCCCUGUUUCCGUGGAGGAAGGCAGACUUCAGACUGAAGGACAGAGAAGGCAACUGCCCUACAGCCCUGCAGGUCUUCAAGUCUGUGGUUGUGGGCACUAACCCAGACAAGAAAAGGAAAGACCUGCAGUAUCGGUGCAGGAAAGGCAAAGAAGGGAACAUCUCAACAUGGAAAAGCUCUACAAAGAAAAUGAAGGAAAGCCAGAGAAUGAAAGAAACCUAGAAAGUGAGGGAAAGCCAGAGGAUGAGGGAAGUACAGAAGAUGAAGGAAAGUCAGACGAGGAAGAAAAGCCGGACAUGGAGGGGAAGACAGAAUGCGAGGGAAAGCGAGAGGAUGAGGGAGAGCCAGGUGAUGAGGGACAACUGGAAGAUGAGGGAAACCAGGAAAAGCAGGGCAAGUCUGAAGGUGAGGACAAGCCACAAAGUGAGGGCAAGCCAGCCUCCCAGGCCAAGCCAGAGAGCCAGCCGCGGGCCGCCGAAAAGCGCCCGGCUGAAGAUUAUGUGCCCCGGAAAGCAAAAAGAAAAACCGACAGGGGGACGGACGAUUCCCCCAAGGACUCUCAGGAGGACUUACAAGAAAGGCAUCUGAGCAGUGAGGAGAUGAUGAGAGAAUGUGGAGAUGUGUCAAGGGCUCAGGAGGAGCUAAGGAAAAAACAGAAAAUGGGUGGUUUUCAUUGGAUGCAAAGAGAUGUACAGGAUCCAUUCGCCCCAAGGGGCCAACGGGGUGUGAGGGGAGUGAGGGGCGGAGGUAGGGGCCAGAAAGACUUAGAAGAUGUCCCAUAUGUUUAAUGUCUUUGGCCUUUAAUUCUGAUUUCUCUGAUGGGAAUAUUGCCAGUCCUGCUUUUCCUGGCAGGCAUUUGCCGGCCUAUGUGCUUUAACCUUAAGCUGAUACUUUCCUUUAGGUGUCACUCUUGUUACCAGCAGACUUUUGACCCAACUACAGUGCUCUGUCUUUUAGUAGAGGAUUUUCACCCAUGUGCAUGGAAUAAAUGUUCAUGGUACAUUGUAAAAUAACAAUAAAAAAGAGUUUUCAGAACCAUG